AGACUGGUGUGGCACGGAGCUGAGGACCGGCCGGAGCUUUGCGGAGGGCCCGGCUUGGCGGGUCCGGGGGGGAGCCGAACCCGCGGGGCACCGGGUCCGGGCGGGGCCGAGCCGGGCCGGGGCGGGAGCCAGCCGGGGUGGGGCGGGGCCGAGGCCGAGGCAGGCGGUCGGCAGUGCUGGGGGUUCAGGUGUUGCGGCGGCUCCACGUAGCCAGGCGGCCCGUGGGCUGGAGCGGGCGGAGCUCGGCCCGCGGCUUGCGUGAGCUCAGGCCGGUCCCAGCGUCCAGAGCGCCGGCCCUUCGGCUUCUUCUAGGCCAUGGCAGGGCCGGGCCCAGGCCCGGGGGACCCGGACGAGCAGUACGAUUUCCUGUUCAAGCUGGUGCUGGUGGGCGACGCAAGCGUGGGCAAGACGUGCGUGGUGCAGCGCUUCAAGACCGGCGCCUUCUCGGAGCGCCAGGGAAGCACCAUCGGCGUCGACUUCACCAUGAAGACGCUGGAGAUCCAGGGCAAGCGGGUCAAGCUGCAGAUCUGGGACACGGCCGGCCAGGAGCGGUUCCGCACCAUCACCCAGAGCUACUACCGCAGUGCCAAUGGGGCCAUCCUUGCCUACGACAUCACCAAGAGGAGCUCCUUCCUGUCGGUGCCUCACUGGAUUGAGGAUGUGAGGAAGUAUGCGGGCUCCAACAUUGUGCAGCUGCUGAUCGAGAUGCAGUCCUGCUAUGUUGCCCAGGCUGAUCUUGAACUCCUGGCCUCAAGCAAUCCUCCUGCCUCAACCUCCAAGUAGUUGGAAUUACAGGUGGAACAAGUCAGACCUCAGCGAGCUUCGGGAGGUCUCCUUGGCUGAGGCACAGAGCCUGGCUGAGCACUAUGACAUCCUGUGUGCCAUUGAGACGUCUGCCAAGGACUCGAGCAACGUGGAGGAGGCCUUCCUGAGGGUGGCCACGGAGCUCAUCAUGCGGCACGGGGGCCCCUUGUUCAGCGAGAAGAGCCCCGACCACAUCCAGCUGAACAGCAAGGACAUCGGAGAAGGCUGGGGCUGCGGGUGCUGACCAGGGGCCGGGCCGGCAGACUGGGGGUUCCCCACCUCCUUGCUCUCCCCAGCCUGCCAAGCCCAGCCCUCCAGAGCCAGCCCUCCUGGGUACCGGCAACUACAGCAGCCGGGUGAAGCUCUGGAGCUCUGCAUCCUGUGGCCUGGCUGCGGGAUGGAGGCUCUCCUUGAGGAAGGGGAAGCAGGAUACCCUGGCGGGCCACCCUGCCAGCCAGCAGCUGGCCCUCCACCAUCUUCACAUUCCAAGACUGGCCUGAACCCGCCGGUGUGGGCCACAGUAGGAGGGGCCAGCAGUCCUCCCUGUCCCAUGCCUGCUGGCUCUGACCGUUUCCUCUCAUGGGUUUGCUUUACCUGUGGCAGCAGGUUGCUGCUUUCCAGGGAUGUGUCCAGUGCCCUGGGUUCUUCCCGGUCAUCCUGGGGCUCUGCACAGAGCAGCAGAGCUAGAGCCAUGAGACCCACAGACUUGGUGCCUGAGCGCAGCUCCAGGGAAGCCCCAGCCCCUUCCAGGCGGGGAACCUGCUUCCUGCCUUCACUGCCCCCGCAGCACUCACAGACAUCUCCCUGGGGUCUGGCUCACUGCCUUAUCAGGACCUCUGAGUUUUCUGACUUUCUGUGUAGCUUCUCAUUUUCAUCAGCACAGCAUGGGGUCACGGCCCACAGCUAGGUGGGGUCACGGCCCACAGCUAGGUGGGGACUGUCUGCUGGCUCAGGGCCCAGUGUUUUGCCACUCAGGUUGCAAAAUUAGCUAAUCCUUCAGUGCCAGCACUCAGAAGUCUGGCAGGUGGGGGAAUGAGAUGAGAAAGUGGACAUUUAAGGUCCAAGUAGAAGCUUGCAUCCUUGAGGCUCAGGGAUGAGAGGGCACCGCAAGGCACCCAGCCUUACCCCACAAGCAGGAAUCCUGCCAGCCGAGCGUGGGUCCCAGUCUAUGGAAUCGAGUCUCCCAGACAAAAAAGGAGAGGCCCUGGCGGUCCUUGGCCUGGCCCAUUUUAUUCCCUGGACCCUUAACUGCCUCACCCUGAGCUGGGCACCAAGGUUAGAAGGCAAAAGUGGGGUAGGGGGAUGUGGGAAGCAGCAUUGUCCUCUGGGCAUGUGGCUCAGAGGUAUCACAGUGACAAAAGAGCCAGGGCUAGGGCUGGAGGGGCCAGGUGAUCUUCCUUAGCCAAUCCCAGUCCGUCUGUGUCAGCCCAGCUCUGCCUCGCAGCCCCCUCAGCAUGGGUGCCCCCAGAAGUAAGCAGCUCUUGGACCCACGAGCAGGGCUGCGUCGGUUUGUGGUCUAGCUCCCAGGGGCAGGCCAGGCAUGGCUCAGUGCAGUCCCUGGGCCAGUGAGAGGCCUCCCCCAUGCCUCCCUGCCCUCUGCACUAAGCACUUUCCAGGCAGGCCUGGCCAUAGGGCAAGAGCAGGCCUUACAGCAGUGCCACGGUGACCCAAGAGGCAGGGUUGGGGCCUGGACAGGGUUUCCUCUGCUGAGACUGAGACAAGCAGGGCUUGAUGCUGGUGGUGGAGCCAGCAUCUCACCUGCCAGGCUUCCUUUUGGGCAGGGAGGCUACCUGUGGAAUGGCUGAGCCUGGUUCUGCAGGGGAGGAAGGCUGCCAGGAGCUGAGGGGCUAGCACCUGCAUUGAGGGGAGUCUGGGUGCAUCAGAUUGGGGGGCGCCAGAGGCGAGGCUGCCUGGCUCCCUUUCUCAGCAGCUUUGCUUGUGGCAGGGGUGAGAGUGGAGCUGAGUGGGGUCUGGGCUCUGCCCCUGCGCCUCCACUGCAGUGCCUGGGCUCCCCUUGCAGGGCAGACAGUGCCUGGCACUGAGGGGUGCCCCCAGACCCCGCUGGGACUGGAUGUGCCGUGGGCAGUGCCUUCCUCCAGCCUCACAACCUUUCUGCUGGGGCUGAAGUUUCUGGGGUCACAUGGUCAGAAGGGGCUGAGCUGGUCUUUCACUGCAGGCCCACUCUGAAAGAGAAAUCCCAUGAAGCCUGUCCUUGCAGAGCCCCUCUGUUUUUGGGGGAACAGGGAGCAUUCACAGGGUCUUGGGAACAAAGGCCUGGGCCUCCCCGUUUGAAUUUCAGCCCCAGUUCCAGGGCAAGUCCCAGCCACCCAAGCAUACUUACCAGUACUGCCCACCACCACCCACUGCCCACCUCUAAGAAGCCCGGCUCUCCUACUCUGCUUCCAGGCUGGGGCCUCACAGGUGGGGCUGUUACCUUCCUCAGGGCUUAGGGAGGGAGGGAGGACAUGGACAGGGCCUUCCACCCUGGCUCCUUCACAGGGAUGGUAGCUGACCGGUGAUGGGUUCAUUUGUCACCUUGGACUGUGAGCCACUUCCACUUCUCGCCCCCCAGGCAGGAGCACCCUCACUCCAAGGGCUUGGCCUGGAAAGGCAGGCUCACCUGGGACUCAACGUUCCUUCCCCCGCCGCCACUGUGCCCCCCGUCCCUCCACCCCAGAAGCCCUGACCUCAUUUGGGCACCUUGCUGUCCUCUGGGCUUCUCCUCUGCCCAGGUCACCCUGUGGCAGGCCUGGGCCCUCAGGAUGUUUCAAAGGCUCCACAGCUCCACCGCUCCACCUGGCUUCACUCCAGCACCCUGUCCCUGGAGCACCUCUGUCCUGUCUGGGCCAACCUGGUCUCCCUGCCCCAUGCCCUCCCCUGGCUCUUAGCAACCUGCCCUUUUAUUCAUGCCAUUUGGGGUCACAGAUGCCUAGCUGGACACAGCUCCCAGAACUGGCUCCACCCUGGGGCCUUGCCCCUAGUACCCCCUGGCAGGAGCAACCCACCCCAUGGUCGAGGUUCCCCUACCCCUGGAUCCUGGACUGAAGCCAUUUCCUACAGAGAAGCGUUCCCACCCCCUCUCAGGCACAAAAGCCGGUGUCCAGGGACUCAAGACCUGUACCUGGGGUUGCAGGGGCUCCUGCCCUGCUGUAUCCCACCAGGAGGGGGCCCCACUGCCCUUCCGGCCCUUAAAACUGGGCUGGGAGAGAAGACGGGGAAGUGUGUGAGACAAAACAAAGCCGGCUUGUUUCCUCCCCUUGGCAGGCUAAGCUCUCCCGGCAGCCCGGGCUCUGGGGCGGAAGGAGAACAGUGUCAUCUCUUCCUUUGUUGAUAAAUUGCCAAAGAGUGGGAACAGGUGGGGUCAGGGGCCAGAGUGCAGGGGAGGGGGCAAUGGUGGAGGUGGCGGGGGGAAGCAGAGGGAGGUGGGCUGAGGCCUCGGUGGGGCCAGUGCGACGCUGGCUUAAGGAGCUGGAGGGGUUCCUAAUACACAUUUAAUUCAGUUUCUCUUCCCUAAGAGGCUGCCGGAGUUGGGGCCUCCUCCAGCAGAGACCCUCGGACCCCUGCAGGGCCUGGACUUGGGGUGAACAGGGCUUCAGUCAGCGCAAGUAUUCCAUUUGCAUUUGGUAAUUUUUCAUGCCACCUAUUUAUGAAUAUAUAAAUCUUUAUACCAAAUCUAUUUUUUAAAACAUGGAAAAGUUGCCUUUAUGGAAACUUGGCAGAGCCAGAGUGUACACAUUCCUAAACCAUUAAACAGAUUUCUAUAACAAG